GCCUUCGCAGUUUCCGUGUUGUGAUGGAACCCUGGACCCACUUUUGUUAACUCUUGAACUUUGUGUCUUUAUUUCUUUUCUCAUUCCUUCAUUUCCACCGGGAAGGGGAGAACACGCAUGUGGUGUAGCGGGCUGGUUCCCCUACAUCUUUGGCACCCAGUGUGGGCUCCUUGUACCCAGGUGGAGUUACACCUGAGCAUGGUCAUUGCGGAGACCAGUCUGUCGAGGGACUCCCAAGAACGUGUGGUCGGCCUUGCGGUAAGCUUGUGUGCUCGGAGUAUUCCAGGGACACCAUGGGACAAUCGGGAAGUAAGCACUCUGCUUACUUACACUUUAUCAAACUCCUCUUAAAGAGGGGGGUAAUAAAGGCUAGCACAGAAAACUUGAUUACUCUGUUUCAAACAGUAGAGCAGUAUUGCCCUUGGUUUCCUGAAUAAGGUACCAUGGAUUUAAAAGAUUGGGAGCAGGUUGGAAUUGCCUUAAAACAAGUUCAUAAGGAAGGAAAACUUAUUCUUCUAACGGUCUGGUCAGACUGGGCUAUGGUUAAAGCAGCCUUGGAACCGUUUCAAAUGGAAAACGAGGUUUAUCCUCCGGCAGAAAGAAUUCCAGCGGAGGAAGGCGGUGCUGCCGCCAAUAUAAAUAUAAAGGAAGUUGAAGGAGGAGAGGAUAGUGAAGAAGAUUUUGAGGAAAGUACAGACAAACCUGGAGAUGACUUAAUUUCUUUUGAGGAGCAUGUGGGACCUCCAGCUGCUCCUAAAAUAGAGAAGCUAUUUAUGCCAAUAUGUUUAAAACAAAGAAGGGCCUUGAGGAAUCUUUGGCUCCUCAUUGGGAUCAUCCGGAGUGGCCACCUCCAAUAAGGCAACGUAACCUGGAGCCUUGGAGGUUUGAAUCUCCAAUUUGCCCUGUUUCACGAAUGGAUAAAUUAGGGGCUCAGGAAUCAAGAACACGUUUUGCAGCACCAGUACAGCAUAGGGCUGCACUGCCACCUAAUGUCAAUGAAUCACCAUUUCAAAUGGUUAUUCGGCAGGCUAGGUUAGCUGGAGAUCCCGAUGCCUGGCAGUUUCCAGUAGUUUUGGAACUCCCACAGCAGCAGGGUGGUGCCCAUCAGGCGGUAUGGGAACCAUUUUCUUUUAAGCUGCUUAAAGAUCUCAAAGCAGCUGUUGGUCAGUAAGGUCCCAAUUCGCCUUCUGUCCAGUCACUAUUACACUCAGUAACUCAGGACAAGCGAUUGGCCCCGGACGAUUGGGAGAUUUUAGCAAAAGCUACUCUUUCGCCCUCCCAAUUUCUUCAAUUUAAAAGUUGGUGGACCGAUGAGGCUCAAAAUCAAGAUCAAAAAAACCGUGCUGCUAAUCCUGUUGUUGCCAUUUCACUUGAACAACUGUUGGGAGUUGGGGGCCAAUGAGGAACUGUACAACAAUUAGUGCUUCAGGAUGAUGCCGUUGAGCAAAUUCGCAAUUGUUGCUUGAGGGCAUGGGAAAAAAUUCAGGACCCGGGAACUACUUAUCCCUCUUUUAAUUCUGUCAGACAAGGCUCAAAAGAACCGUAUCCUGAUUUUAUUGCUCCUCUUCAAGAUGCAGCUCAGAAGGCUCUCACUGAUGAAAGUGCCAGGAAGGUGAUUAUAGAAUUCUUGGCUUAUGAAAAUGCCAACCCUGACUGUCAAUCACCUAUUCGCUCUGUGAAAGGAAAGGUUCUGGUGGGAGUUGAUGUAAUCAAUGAGUAUAUCAGGGCAUGUGAUAGAUUGGUGGAAUCAUGCAUAAGGCUAUGAUAAUGGCUCAAAACAUGGCAGGAUCAAAGGUGGGAGAUCCAGUGAAAAACUUUUCAGGCAAUUGUUAUAACUGUGGGCAAUUUGGAAAUACAAAAAAGGAAUAUAAGAACAAAUCAAACAAACAAUCCAGAUCUAAUCAAACAAAGGAGCCACCUGGCUUAUGUCCCAGGUGCCAGAAGGGUAAAUGUUGGGCUAAACGGUGUCACUCCAAAUUUGAUGAAAAUGGCCAACCCUUGCAGGCGCAAUUGGGAAAUGGGAAGAGGGGCCAGCCUCAGGCCCCACUCCAAACUGGGGCAUUCCCUCUCCAGCAGUUUGUCCGUCAGUGGGCACCAGUGCCCUUAAUCCCUCAAGUGACCACCACAGUAACAUAAUUGGCGCCAGUUACAACAGGGGGCGCUGCUUUAGAUUUAUGUUGCACCAGAGCUGUGUCUCUGCUUCCAGGGGAACCACCUCAAAAGGUGCCCUCUGGAGUAUUUGGCCCUUUACCUGAGGUAACAGUUGGACUUGUUUUAGGGAGAUUUAGUCUAAAUUUAAAAGGAGUUCAAAUUUAUACUGGAGUGAUAGAUUCCGAUUUUGUGGGAGAAAUUCAAUUGGUUAUUAGUUCUAGUAUUCCUUGGAGUGCAAGCCAGGCAGAGAGAAUUGCUCAAUUGUUGUUAUUACCUUAUUACCUAAUUGUUGUUAUUACCUAAGUAGGAGAAAGUACAGUAAAAAGAGAAGGUGGUUUCGGCAGCACUGAUAGCAAAGGAAAAGCAACUUAUUGGGUAAGUCAAGUUUCUGAAAAUAGACCUGUGUGCACAAUAACGAUUCAGGGAAAACUCUUUGAAGGACUUGUCGAUACAGGCGCUAAUAUUUCUGUUACAGCCCUGGAUCAGUGGCCAAAAACAUGGCCCAAACAGAGAGCUUCUAUGGGUUUAAUUGGAAUAGGCAUGGCAUCUGAAGUUUAUCAGAGUGUUACAAUUUUACACUGUUUAGUACCAGAUGGACAGGAAGGCACCAUCCAACCUAUAAUUACUGCCAUUCCCAUUAAUUUGUGGGGAAAAGAUUUGUUACAACAGUGGGGUACGGAAAUCACCAUUCCCUCUAUGAUUUACAGUUCAGAGAGUCAAAGCAUGAUGACUAAGUUGGGGUAUACUCCUGGAAAAACAUUAGGAAAGAAUGAGGAUGGAAUAACUCAGCCAAUUGAAGCUUCAGUUAAACUUGACCGAAAAGGAAUUGGGUACUCUUUUUAGGGGCGGCCACUGUUGAGCCUCCAAAGCCCAUCCCAUUGAAAUGGAAAACUCAAAAACCUGUGUGGGUUGAUCAGUAGCCGCCUCCUCAGCAAAAACUGGAGGCAUUACAUUGACUAGCAAAAGAGCAAUUAGACAAAGGACAUAUUGAACCUUCUUUCUCACCGUGGAAUUCCCCGGUUUUUGUAAUUCAGAAAAAAUCCGGUAGAUGGCGCAUGUUGACCAACCUACGAGCGGUUAAUGCAGUCAUUCAACCGAUGUGGGCUCUCCAACCGGGGUUGCCAUCCCCAGUCAUGAUUCCAAGAGAAUGGCCGGUGGUAAUAAUUGAUUUGGGUCGGGCGCGGUGGCUCACGCCUAUAAUCCCAGCAUUUUGGGAGGCCGAGGCGGGAGGAUCACGAGGUCAGGAGAUCAAGACCAUCCUGGCUAACACGGGGAAACCCCAUCUCUCCUAAAAAUACAAAAAAUUAGCCGGGUGUGGUAGCGGGUGCCUGUAGUCCCAGCUACUCCGGAGGCUGAGGCAGGAGAAUGGCGUGAACCCGGCAGGCGGAGCUUGCAGUGAGCGAGAUCGCGCCACUGCAUUCCAGCCUGGGCGACAGAGUGACACUCCAUCUCAAAAAAAAAAAUUUGAUUCGAAAGAUGGUUUUUUCACCAUUCCUUUGGAUCCCCAGGACUUUGAAAAAUUUGCAUUUACAAUAUCUGCUAUAAAUAAUAAGGAACCAGCUACUAGGUAUCAGUGGAAAGUUUUACCCCAAGGAAUGUUAAAUAGUCCUACAAUUCGUCAAACUUUCGUUGGGAAGGUCAUUCAGCCCGUCCAGGAUCAGUUUCCUGAUUGUUAAUAUUAUUCAUUAUGUUGAUGACAUUUUAUGUGCUGCUACAAGUAGGGAUAGACUUAUCAAAUGUUUUUCUAUGUUACAAGAAAUGGUGGGGCUUACAGUUCUCGCUAUAGCGCCAAAUAAAAUUCAAACUACUACACCCUAUCAUUACCUAGGAAUGAAGGUGGAGGAGAGAACAGUUAUGCCUCAAAAGGUAGAAAUUCGUAAGAAGUCCUUAAAAACUUUAAAUGAUUUUCAAAAAUUAUUAGGAGACGUUAAUUGGAUAAGGCCCACCUUAGGAAUUGCCACUUAUGCGAGGUCUGACUUGUUUGCUUUGCUGAGAGGGGAUCCAAAUUUACAUAGCAAAAGAACUCUGACGCCUGCAACAGCUUCAGCUGUUAAGAAUAAUUGAGGAAAAAAUUCAAAGUGCUCAAGUCAGUAGAAUAGAUCCUAGUGUUCCCUUACAGCUCUUGGUGUUCCUACUCUCCAUUCUCUUACAGGAGUGAUUAUUCAAGAUGUUGACUUGGUUGAAUGGUCUUUUUUACCCCACAGUACAACUAGGACUUUUUCAAUUUACUUAGAUCAAAUAGCUAUUCUUAUAGGCCAAGCCCAAUUAAGAAUAGUUAGAUUCACUGGCACAGAUCCAGAUAAAAUUGUAGUUCCUUUAAACAAAGCACAGGUUCAACAAGCCUUUAUACAUUUAUCAGAAUGGCAGUCUAAUUUAGCUGGUUUUGUUGGCCAUAUAGAUAAUCAUUACCCUAAAACAAAAAUUUUUCAGUUCCUAAAAUUGGCUACCUGGAUUUUACCUAAAAUAACCAGUUCUAUCCUCUUGGAGGGGGCUGUAACUGUCUUUACUGAUGGCUCUCAGAAUGGAAAAGCAGCUUAUACAGGACCAGAAGAAAAGGUUAUUCAAACCCAGUUUCAUUCUCCACAAAGAGCUAAGCUACAAGCAGUUAUAUUUGUAUUGGAAGAUUUUGAUCAACCUGUUUAUAUUGUCUCUGACUCUGCCUAUGUGGUUCAGGCGACAACAAUGGUAAAAACAGCUUUAAUAAAAUAUAUUUCUGAUGAUCAGCUAAAUUUUUUGUUUAGUUCACUUCAACAAGCAGUUAGAGUUUGAAAUUUUCCUGUUUAUAUUACACAUAUUCUAGCUCACACAAAUUUACCAGGACCUUUAACCCAAUUAAAUAAUCAAGCAGAUUUAUUAGUGACACUUGUUUUAACAGAGCCUCAAGAAUUCCAUUCAUUAACUCAUGUAAAUGCUGCUGGAUUAAAAAAUAAAUAUUCAUUUACCUGGAAACAAGCUAAAAAUAUAGUGCAACAUUGUCCGCAAUGCCAGGUGCUACAGCUACCUACUCAAGAACCUGGAGUUAAUCCUAGGGGGCUUAAACCAAAUGCUCUUUGGCAAAUGAAUGUGACUCAUGUCCCAUCACUGGGAAAACUUUCUCUUGUGCAUGUUACUGUUGAUAAUUUCUCUUGGUUUAUCUGGGCUACGUGCUAAACUGGAGAAAGUACAGCUCAUGUAAAACGACAUUUAUUAUCUUGUUUUGCAGUCAUGAGUGUGCCACAGAAAAUGAAAACGGACAACGGACAAGGAUAUUGCAGUAAAACUUUUGAAAGUUUUGUUCAGCAAUGGAAAUUUGUACACACUACAGGAAUACCCUAUAAUUUGCAAGGUCAGGCCACAGUAGAAAGGGCCAUUCGGACUCUUAAGACACAAUUGGAAAAACAAAAGAAAGGGGGAAGCAGUAAGGAGUAUACCACGCCCCAUAGGCAGUUACAAUUAGCCCUUUUGACUCUAAAUUUUUUGAACAUUUCCAGAGAUCAGGUCUCCACAGCAGCGGAACAACACUUUUCUGGACAGAAAGUUAAUUUACAUGAAGGAAAAACGGUCUGGUGGAAGGAUACCAGAACUAAAACUUGGGAAUUAAGAAAAAUUAUGACGCGGGGAAGGGCUUUUGCUUGUGUUUCACCAGGAGACAAUCAAACACCCAUUUAGAUACCCAAUAGACAUUUGAAAUUCUGCAAUGAACCCUACACCGACCGGACAGAAGAAAGGGAAGAAUCCAAAGAGGAAGAAGACUGGUCCCUCCGACCUGUCCUUUCGGGAGCUGAGAAAGAUGACGAAGCUGAGCGUCUCAGAGAAACAACAGAAGACGGAGAAGACCCGCCAGGCUACACCACCGACAUGAGAACAGAUAAAGAAGCUGACUCAAAUGGCAGAGGGCAGCCUAAAGGAGAAACAACUGGCAAUUAUCCCGGGUAAUAUGAUCUUGGCUGCCUUGAUGGUAAUUACCGCGGCGGUAAGUCUCCCUGCUGUCUGGACUGAAGAAAAUUUUACAUACUGGCUUCUGUUCCAUUUCCUCCUUUAAUUAGGCCAGUUACUUGGAUGGAUUCCCCUAUUGAAGUUUAUACAAAUGAUAGUAUUUUGGAUGCCUGGGCCGAUUGAUGAUGGCUGUCCUGCACAGCCUGAGAAGGAGGGUAUGUUGAUGAAUGUAACUGGUAUGAAUACCCUCCAAUUUGUUUAGGAAUUGCUCCUUGAUGUUUACCAUUGCAAAUACAUAGUUGGAUAAUCUAUGUACCUCCUCAUAAUCGUUCCCAACCCAGUUAUCACGUAGUGAGUGGAAUGUCUUUCCAACCUAUCAUGACUGUAAAAACUUAUGGGGAUGGUUAUUUUCGGUCAAAUUUAAAAGUAAAAAAUUACAAAUCUCAAGGACUGGCUUGUCCUAAAAGAAAUCCAAAAUGGUCAGAAAAACUAGAGAUUCUUGCUUGGGACAACUGUGUAGCAGAUGGUGCAGUAGUUUUGCAAAAGGAUUCUUAUGGAAUAAUUAUAGAUUGGGCCCCCAAAGGAUCCUUUGCCAGAAAUUGCACUGGACAAAAUGCUGGGUGCGCUGAGGAUUCCUUCAUGAUAGAUUAUAGAGAAAGUCCCAAUAAUCCCCCCACUUUAGUUAGAAGAUUGGAAUCACUAUAUCCAUUGAAAUGGGAAGAUAAAGGUACUGCUCCUCCCUGGCCAAAGAUAAUUAGUCCAGUCAUGGGUCUGGAACAUCCAGAAUUGUGGAAGUUGCUUAUGGCUACCUCCGGAAUGAGAGUGUGGAAAGGGGAAGCAUCAUGGGGAACAAGAGGUAAUAAGCUACUGUUUACCAUGCUUCUUCAGUCUAAUCAGUCUAUUUCUCUUCAAAGUUGUGUUAAACCUCCUUACAUGUUAGUUGUUGGAAAACUUAUCAUUUUACCUGACUCUCAAACCAUUACUUGUGACAAUUGCCAUCUGUUUACUUGUAUUCAUUCUACUUUUGAUAUGAGGAAUAGCAUUUUGCUGGUCCGAGCACGAGAGGGCGUUUGGAUUCCAGUUACUCUUAAUAGGCCUUGGGAGACUUUUCCCUCUAUUCAUGUAAUAACUGGAGUUUUAAAAGGGAUUCUUAAUCGUACAAUAAGAUUUAUUUUUACUUUAAUUGCUGUGAUUAUGGGCUUGAUUGCUGUCACCACCACCGCGGCUGUGGCAGGUGUUGCCUUGCAUUCUUCCAUUCAAACUGCUCAUUAUGUUAAUGCCUGGCAGAAAAAUUCCACCAGAUUAUGGAAUUCUCAGGCAAAAAUUGAUCAGAAGUUGGCCAAUCAAAUUAAUGAUUUGAGGCAAACAGUCACCUGGAUAAGAGAUCGUUUUAUGCAUUUAGAGCAUCGUAUGCAAAUGCAAUGUGAUUGGAAUACAUCUGCUUUUUGUAUUACUCCUUAUUCUUAUAAUGUUACUGAACAUCAGUGGGAAAAGGUCUGAUGCCACUUACAAGGAAGAGAAGAUAAUCUAACCCUGGAUAUAACUAAAUUAAAAGAACAGAUUUUUGCAGCAUCGCAGGCUCACUUAAAUUUGUUGCCUGGAGCAGAAAUGCUUGCUGGAGCUGCAGAUAGGCUCUCGGAGCUCAAUUCUAUCAAAUGGAUUAAAACUCUGGGAAGCUCUGCCAUUGCUAAUUUUGUUUUAAUUUGUGUCUGCUUAUGUUGUCUGUUUUUAGUCUGCAGAUGCGGAAGGCAGCUCCUGAAAGAAAAUCAAAACCACAAGCAAGUUAUGAUUGAGAUGGCUGUUUUAAAUUUAAAAAAUGGGGGAAAUGUGGGUCAAAACAGGGGCUUGGAUGUGGGCCGAGGUGGUUGAGGGCUGGCCUAUGGUGUGCCUGUUUAAGGAUUAACAAAAUAUGCUUUAGAAUAGUGCUUUAUUAAUAUAGUCAUGAAUCAUAAGAAUAGCUUCUGCUUAGUCCGACAAUAUAAGAAUCAGGCGGUGAGCUUGCUUGCCUAACUGCAGGGUGGAACAAACAACCACAGGAAGUGUGCGGAGCCUCUAAGCAAGAAAGCUUGCUUAUUGCUCAACCUCCCACUUGAGUCCCUGAACAAAGGUCUUGUGGGAAGGGAAGCGACCCCUGCUCCAUUCCCCAGAAGGGAACAGCAGGAGGUUGCUUGUAAAAGAGGAGAAGUCCUCUGAGGAUAAGGGGAAAGUCUUCUAUCUCUCGCUCGUUCCCAGAGGCAGAGAGCUCUGCUGCCCUGCUGAUGGUGCUUGGAGUGGACCGCUCCUUUGAUGCACAGGCCUGUGGUCUGACGGGCUGUCUGCUUUCACGUCCUGUUCUGUUAACCAAUUAGUUGGACUUUAAGGAUUAUCUGUAAGUUAAACAUAGAGUAUUAGCUUAUACAGUGGAACAGUAAAUAAUAUUAACUUGCUGAUGACGCAUGCUACCCCCUCUGCCACCUCUCCCCAUGGUCACCCUGUGAUCACCCCACCAUCUGCCCACCCUCAGCCUAUAGGAUCAAAGGAACUGUACUCAGUAAAUAUCAGUGGAAUCCAGAGCUCAGGGCUGUCGCAGUUUCCACAUUGCGAUGGACCCCUGGACCCACUUUUGUUAACUCUUGAACUUUGUGUGUUUGUCUUUAUUUCUUUUCUCAUUCCCUCGUCUCCACUGGGAAGGGGAGAACCCGCGGGUGGUAUAGCGGGCUGGUUCCCCUACAAGGUUGACCAAACUUUUUCUGUAAAAGACCAGAUAUUAAAUAUUUUCAGCAUUGUAUGCUAUACAUUCUGUUGCAACUUCUCAACUCUGUGGUUAUAGAAUGAAAGCAGCUACAGACAGUAUAUAAACAAAUGAGCAUGCCUAUAUUCCAAUAAAACUUUAUUUGUAGACACUGAAAUUUAGAUUUCAUAUAAUUUUCACAGGUCACAGGAUAUCGAUCUAUUUGUGAUUUUUUUCAACUACUUAAAUAUAUAAAAAUGGACCAUGGGUCGAGUUUAGACUGUGGGCGAUACAAUAGUUUGUUGACCUCUGAUGUAGAGCACUAAACACUUAAGUUCUUAGAUAAUUAAUGUUAGGUCAGAGGAGAAAUUAGCAAUGGAAGAAAAUUCAGUUUCAUUACUUUACAGGAUGGUUAUUUUAUGAGUACUAUUUUGAACUAAUAGAAAGAGAGGGUAUAAAGCCAAUGUAACCGAAUGAUAUUUGUAGGUAUUAGUUUGUACCAUAUAUUUUCUUUCUUUUUUUUUUUUUUUUUGAGACAAAGUCUCACUUUGUCACCAGGCUGGAGUGCAAUGGCACAAUCAUGGCUCACUGCAACCUCCACCUCCCAGAUCCAAGUGAUUCUCCUGCCUCAGCCUCCCAAGUAGCUGGGACUACAGGCAUGCACCACCACGCCCAGCUAAUUUUUGUAUUUUUAGUAGAGACAGGGUUUCACUAUGUUGGCCAUGAUUGUCUCGAUAUCUUGACCUUGUGAUCCACCCACCUUGGCCUCCCAAAGCGCUGAGAUUACAGGCAUGAGCCACCAUGCACAGCCACUGUACCAUAUAUUUUCUUAUAUACUGGAUUUUGUUUUUCCCCAUUCAGACUAGAGGUAGGCAUGCAUUUCCUCUGCGGAUUGUCACAGCCAGCAAUAUUAGAAACAACAGAUGAAAAAAGAUUAAAAUCAGAGAAGCUCCCACUCCCACAAUUUGCCGGGGUGGAAAGAGGAUGAAUUGGUGGGAAAUCAAAAGAAUGUGAUGUUUUCCCUUGCAUUGCUGAAAAGGAAGCGGGGGGAUUUGCGGCAGCAAUCUGUGUAGUCCCUCAGGCUGAGGUCCCAGUGACUAGAGCAAGAAUAGACAGUUGUAGUGAUAUUAUACCAACUUCACACCACCCCAAACCCCAGAAAUCAUAUGCAACCCCCAGACUGGAGAGAAACUCUAAAUUGUCUGAUAUCAUGCUGAAAGCAGUAGAGAAUCAGAUUUCUCUGAGCCCAUGGAAUGGAGCCUUGAAAUUCAAUUAGAAAACAGCUGCAGUUAUUUCACAUGUAAAUUGUCAAAAGACACAUAUCCGCUUUACUAACAUAGAACAAGUAUCAGUUACCUGAAUGCUCUCAAGCCUCGAAGUUGGUGGGGAAACCAUGUUUCCAUUACAUCUACAGUGGGAAACCUAACCUCACUUGCUGGCACCUUCCAGGAUCUUUGGAGUCAAUGUUUUUCUAUUAUUUCCUGCUUUUACUGAAUUACUGUAAUUUCUCUCAAGUCUAGCCUCUUUUGGCUGUUCUUUUUCUCCACUCUGCAUCAUUCCCAAAGCAACAGCCUCUUUCCCUCUUCUCAAAAUGCUGCAGAUACAAGGCAUCUCUGUGUAGUAGAUUCUUACGGAAGAUUCAGGCAGGGGAAGAGGAAGAGGAAUUUAGGCUGCACCAAACAUCUUAAAACUGACUAUUUAAAGAUCCUUGCUCUUUAAAGAUCCUUGGCCAUAGCCCAGAACUUCUCCCUGGCUGCCUCUUGCUCAGCUCCCUGGCAUCUUGAUGUAUUCCUUCCUCACAUCCUCCUCCCCAUUCUUAUCUCAUUCACUCCUUCCUUUUUCACACCUUUCUUCUUGGGUUACCUAAGGAAACUCGAAAAUCUUCAUUAAUUCUUCAUUAACAGAAUAAUUUUGCCCUUCUAGUUUCACUGCUAGCCUAUUUCAGCCAGGCCUAUUAUUAAACACUGUUCUUCCUCUAUGACUAUGCUAAUGAGUAUGACCUAUUUCCUCACCAUGGAGUUCUGAGAAAUUAUUUCUUUUUUGAAAGCUAAAAUUAAUUGCACAAGGCCCUGAACAAUCCUGAUUAGCAGAUAUUGUGAGAAGAGACAUCUCCAUUUCCCUGACAUCCCCUCCCAUUAUAUUCAAGAGAAGAACAGGGCAUGGCUAACUCGGUUCUUAGGGGCCAGUGUUCAUUCCAAACCCACAGUGCAGGGAGGAAUUAGAGACCACAUGUGGCUCUCUAGAUGGGUCCCAUUUUUUUGCUUGUUUGUUAUAUUCCCAAUAUUUUGUCAUUUUUAAAAACAUUCUCAUGUGGUCUGGGGCCAUCCAUCAUUACCUUCUGCAGCAAUAAUUCCACUUCUGAUCUGGUGAAAGCUUCUCAUGGAUUGUGUGUGUGUCUAUGUGUGCGUGUGUAUGUCUGUAUCUGUGUGUGUGUUGGAUGACAGAACUAUAGAGGAUUGGGAAGAUGUGGAGAUAAAGAUUCUCCUGGUGAUGUUACGCUCCAAGUUCAGAUUGCCAUCAGUGGCUUGGGCUUCCACUCUGCUUCUUUCUUCCACUCUUCACCUCUGAUUCAUCUAGAUCCCUGCACAGGCUGGAAUUAUGUUCUAAGCCUGGGAACCCCACAGCCUCUGUGUAAAGCUAACAAAGCCCAUAGCAAAUGGAUAAGACCCUGCUUCUAGAACAGUCUACUUCAAGUCAAAUCGUGGCAUAUAUGAUGUUAAGCAAGUUGCUUGCUCUCUUUAUGUCUCAGUCACCUCACUGGGAAAAUGGGAAUUAAAAAUAAUAAUACAUAUCUCAAAGGGCUACUCUGGAGAUUACAUGAAUUAGUACAUAGGAAGUGUUCAGAGAGUACCUGGCUCAUAGUAAGUGACUUCUAAAUGUUGACACUUAAUUUAAGUUUACAGAGAAGGCUCUGUGCCAAUACUGACUUAGGGCUACAAGGUCUCAGGAUCCAUUCCCACACUCAGAUUUUAACCAUUGAUUUCAAAGCACCCACACAUGCCAGGUUGGCUGGCUCAUGAUGGCUUUAGCCAUUGGGACCACCUGAGCGGCUUCUGGAUACUGACACUGGGACUAGCUAGAUCACCACAUAAAAGAAAUCAGAUUUUAGCUUGUUGAUUGUUGACUUGAUGGAGAACUUCUAAGCCUUUUUAAGUAGAGAAGUAAUGUGGUCUUUUUUUGCAUCAAGAUAAUGUUUUAUACUCUGUAGCAGAUGGUCUGCAUGAGGAAGAAACUGGGAGCAGAUUGAUCAACUAAGAGAUACCAGUAGAUUAUGCCAAGGUGAUGAACACAUGAAUUAAGGUGACAGCAGCAAUGGCGCUGAUGGAGAGAAUUUACCAUUUAGAAGGUAGAAUCAGCAGAACUUAUUGACUAACUGGAAAUGCAGGAUGAGGAGGAGGAAUGUUCUCUGAUAAUCCCAAGAUUUUGAAGUGGGUAAAUGAAGUGAGUAAAUGCUGGUUUUGCCAACUCACUAUCUUCUUUCGAAGGCAAGCCUUUCUUCCCAAGGGGAGGGAAGAGGAAGAGAAGAGACUAUAAUAAAUUUAGUCUGAGCUAACAGGCUACUGGACAAACACUUCUGGAGUUACAGAGAGAAGUAAUAGCUGGAAUGAAAUAUUUGGGAGUUGUUAAACACUAACAUUCAAUGGACCAAAAAGGAAAGAAUACUCCAUAAAGGAAAGAUGGAAAACUUGGAGGAUGCCCAGAGAACUAAGAGGGAUGGGUUUUAUAAAAGCCUGUGGAAGAAGAACUUUUGAGGAAGAAGGAGCAGCCUGAGAAUUCAGCGAGAAACUGCCAUGAGGAGUGUUGUGGCAUCUUGUAAGCAGCCGCAAUUGCAGUAAAGGAGUCAGAAGUCACUGGCUUUAAUUGAGGAGUUCAUGGAAAGAGAGACCGUGGAAUCAGUGAGUGUGGACUGUCUUCUUAAAAAAUAAGCAUAGUUGAAAUGGAGAGAAAAAUAGGAAAGUUACUAGAGGCAGGAGUAAGAGAGAUUUUAAUUUUCUAGGGUUUAAUAGACUUGGGCUUGUUCAUAGAGUAAAAAGGGGAAACAACUGUGGAAGGAAAGGGUGAAGUCAAUAGUGAAAAAGAGGAAGGUAAUCAACCUAGCUCUAGAGAAGAAAUGAGGAGCUGGGGAUUAAAGCACACGUGGAAGGAUCAUAGUACAACAGGUGGAAUCAAUACCACAGAAGCAACCCUCAAGCAACAAGGACCUGGGGUUGGUGGAUAUAUACCUACUCUUGGUCUCCUGCCACCUGAGAGGAAAAUUCUGAUGUGGGGCUCUCAGAGGUUUCAGUAGGUUGGAGCCUCAGUUGUCUAUGAGUGUACCCCCACUCAUUAGGUACUUUUUGGCUUUCCUCCCUGUUCUAUUUCAUUUGACCACACCCUUGUUUAUGCUCCCUGGAAUCACCUCCCAAAUAAACUACUUGUAUCCAAA